CUACCUGCUCCACCCUCAACCCACCAGAACCAUGGGCUGCUGUGGCUGCUCUGGAGGCUGUGGCUCCGGCUGUGGGGGCUGCGGCUCUGGCUGUGGGGGAUGUGGCUCUAGCUGCUGUGUGCCCAUCUGCUGCUGCAAGCCCGUGUGCUGCUGUGUGCCAGCCUGUUCCUGCUCCAGCUGUGGCUCCUGUGGGGGCUCCAAGGGGGGCCGUGGCUCCUGUGGGGGCUCCAAGGGGGACUGUGGCUCCUGUGGGGGCUCCAAGGGAGGCUGUGGUUCUUGUGGCUGCUCCCAGUGCAGCUGCUAUAAGCCCUGCUGUUGCUCCUCAGGCUGUGGGUCAUCCUGCUGCCAGUCCAGCUGCUGCAAACCCUGCUGUUCCCAGUCCAGCUGUUGUAAGCCCUGCAGCUGCUCUUCAGGCUGUGGGUCAUCCUGCUGCCAGUCCAGCUGCUGCAAGCCCUGCUGUUCCCAGUCCAGCUGCUGUAAGCCCUGCUGCUGCUCUUCAGGCUGUGGGUCAUCCUGCUGCCAGUCCAGCUGCUGCAAGCCCUGCUGUUCCCAGUCCAGCUGCUGUGUCCCAAUUUGCUGCCAGUGCAAGAUCUGAGGCUCUGCCUACAAAUCUCAGCUGGUCCCACAGAUCUGGGCUCUCCAGGAAUGACUGUAGCUGUGUCCUGAAUUCCUGAAGCACAUCUCUGAGUCUGUCCUCCUCUGGACUAAGGCAGCCUAGCGUCCAGGGCUCAGUACUCAGCUGCUCAGCCUCUGAGGUCAUGAGGGCUUCUGGCAUGCUGGGUGCUGCCCAUCAACCCUCCCAGAAUCCCCUCUUCCUUUCCUGACCUCAUCACUUCAACCUUCUCAGGGCUUCAAGAUCCCACAUCCCUGGGCCCCUCCUGUGAGCCUGCUGGAAACACACUGAAACUGGAAUCCUCCGACCUGCUGCCGCCUCUCCCCGGUCCCUGCAACCUCCUGGCUCCUCCACCCUUCAUCUUCAUCCUGCCUGAGCUGCCACAGCUCCGAUUGUUUUUGGAGUUGACCUAGAGGACUCAGAAUUAUUAGAGACCCCAGGAUCCUCUCCUGAGGAGGAGGGGCGCCCAGUCUCCUCUUCUACCUCUGACCUGGCCUUGUUUCUUUCCCCAGGGCUUCGCCUUGUAAGUGCCUAGGCUGAAUCUUCUAAAUAAAUACGAUCCACACCUCCCA